AGAUCUCCGGGCCUCCGCGGCCAUAGCUGACUGUGCCGUCCCUUCCCCUCACCCGCUCCACGCCCUCCUGGGCCGAGUGGAGUUGGGUGGUGUCGGGAGCCUCUCCCUGAGGGGCACCGCGUCUUCAGGAGCUGGGCCUCCAGUGCGGCGCGAUGUCAGGCGCGGUGACAGCUCUGUGAGUCCGAGGCCGCGGCCGUGGCGCUGGGCGGCUGCGGGGCCUGACCGGUCCGCUCAUGGUGCCGCCACGACGCCAUCGCGGGGCAGGAAGGCCAGGUAGGCAGGCAGGGAAGGGCCCCGACAUCACCGGAGCCCAAACCGGGACGGAGUGCCCACCAGCAGCACCACCUCCUGCCCUCGGUGGCAGCAGGAGCGCCUUGACCGAAACCGUGAAGGUCUCUAGGGGCGGAGGGAGCGGGAGCUGACAGGGGCGCCGGAGCCCUGCGCCCACCGCUGGCAAUUGAGGAAGCCGUGCGUGCGCCCUCGCCUCGGCUCCCCGGGGAGGCGUCGCUGCCUUAACUGUCUUCCCCGCUCCAAAACAGAAGGAUGAUUUCUUUUCCCAGCUGUUUCUUUUAAAAUGACUGGAUGUUUUGAUAGAGGUGGGUGGAGGAGCAUGGAGAAUCCUUUUCUUUUACCACUUGAAGAGAUUGGAAAGGUGCCUUCAAGACCCACAGCAAAUCACUUACUCUCCGAUAACCAAAUUCCACUCCAGCAGAUCAGGGACAGAAAAGACACUUUUAGAAACAGUGUCUAGACGCUGUCCCCAGGGAUGGAUUCCUCUGGAUGGAGAGGGGUGCUGAGUUCUUCACCUCCUUUUAGACUGAGAUCUGCCAAGUUUUCCGGCAUUGCUCUUGAGGAUCUCAGAAGGGCUCUUAAGACAAGACUGCAAAUGGUGUGUGUAUUUGUCAUGAACCGAAUGAAUUCCCAGAACAGUGGUUUCACUCAGCGCAGGCGAAUGGCUCUUGGGAUUGUUAUUCUUCUGCUUGUUGAUGUGAUAUGGGUUGCUUCCUCUGAACUUACUUCGUAUGUUUUUACCCAGUACAACAAACCAUUCUUCAGCACCUUUGCAAAAACAUCUAUGUUUGUUUUGUACCUUUUGGGCUUUAUUAUUUGGAAGCCAUGGAGACAACAGUGUACAAGAGGACUUCGCGGAAAGCAUGCUGCUUUUUUUGCAGAUGCUGAAGGUUACUUUGCUGCUUGCACAACAGAUACAACUAUGAAUAGUUCUUUGAGUGAACCUCUGUAUGUGCCUGUGAAAUUCCAUGAUCUUCCAAGUGAAAAACCUGAGAGCACAAACAUUGAUACUGAAAAAACCCCCAAAAAGUCUCGUGUGAGGUUCAGUAAUAUCAUGGAGAUUCGACAGCUUCCGUCAAGUCAUGCAUUGGAAGCAAAGUUGUCUCGCAUGUCAUAUCCUGUGAAAGAACAAGAAUCCAUACUGAAAACUGUGGGGAAACUUACUGCAACUCAAGUAGCGAAAAUUAGCUUUUUUUUUUGCUUUGUGUGGUUUUUGGCAAAUUUGUCAUAUCAAGAAGCACUUUCAGACACACAAGUUGCUAUAGUUAAUAUUUUAUCUUCAACUUCCGGACUUUUUACCUUAAUCCUUGCUGCAGUAUUUCCAAGUAACAGUGGAGAUAGAUUUACCCUUUCUAAACUAUUAGCUGUAAUUUUAAGCAUUGGAGGCGUUGUACUGGUAAACCUGGCAGGGUCUGAAAAACCUGCUGGAAGAGACACAGUAGGUUCCAUUUGGUCUCUUGCUGGAGCCAUGCUCUAUGCUGUCUAUAUUGUUAUGAUUAAGAGAAAAGUAGAUAGAGAAGACAAGUUGGAUAUUCCAAUGUUCUUUGGUUUUGUAGGUUUGUUUAAUCUGCUGCUCUUAUGGCCAGGUUUCUUUUUACUUCAUUAUACUGGAUUUGAGGACUUCGAGUUUCCCAAUAAAGUAGUAUUAAUGUGCAUUAUCAUUAAUGGCCUUAUUGGAACAGUACUCUCAGAGUUCCUGUGGUUGUGGGGCUGCUUUCUUACCUCAUCAUUGAUAGGCACACUUGCACUAAGCCUUACAAUACCUCUGUCCAUAAUAGCUGACAUGUGUAUGCAAAAGGUGCAGUUUUCUUGGUUAUUUUUUGCAGGAGCUAUCCCUGUAUUUUUUUCAUUUUUUAUUGUAACUCUCCUAUGCCAUUAUAAUAAUUGGGAUCCUGUGAUGGUGGGAAUCAGAAGAAUAUUUGCUUUUAUAUGCAGAAAACAUCGAAUUCAGAGAGUUCCAGAAGACAGCGAACAGUGUGAGAGUCUCAUUUCUAUGCACAGUGUUUCUCAGGAGGAUGGAGCUAGUUAGCUGUCUGUUGUCUGUAGCCCAGCUUGAUAAUGGAACUAUACAGCGAAGAGACAAUCUCUGGCAAGUUUUUGUAGAAAAAAUGUUUCAGUGCCUAGUCUGAAAAAUAACAGUUUGAGUUCUUUGAAACUCUAAAAUAUAUUUUUCUCAUACCUGUUUUCUUCAUUUUCAUAAUGAAGCACUUUGCUAUGUAGCUGUGUACAUAUCACUACAGUUAUAGGAAGUUUCAGUCUACAGUCCAUCCAAAGGACCAACCUGCCUUACACAUCUCAAGGAAUUCAGCUGUUGAAAUCAUUUGAACUAAUCAAGGAAUAAAUCCUAAUGUUCUGGGACUUUAUUUUCACAUGUUAAAUGCUGGAAUAUAUUAUGAAAAUGUUUUCAAGAAAUCACUUAAGUGUUCAUAGACCAGUAUUUCUGACAGGUAAAAUGCUAAAAUAAGCUACCUGUAAUAAGUGUGGAUUAUAUUUUUGGGUUUUGUAGAAUAUUGCAAAUUAACCACACAAAAAAUGUUUAAUUUAUGCAACAAGCAUGUUUGUGCAAAUUUCAUGGGACUUUAAAAAGAAUAAGUAUUUGAGAAAAUAUCUGGUUCACUUACACUACAUUUACUGUAUUAUUCUUUUAUAGCAUUAGGUGCCUUGUAUUUUAAAUCUGUGACAAACCAUGGCAAAUUUUUAAAGGGGAAGUAUUAUUAUAAAAUGAAGAAAUAUGUAUUUCUAAAGGCUAUAUUGCUGUAAACUUAAUUGAUAAAGCUCUGUUUAAUUUAGAGUUUUGAAGAAAUAGUCUCCCUUCAAUUAAGAAAUUUUCAUAAUGGAAUGAUUUAAAUUGAAGUGACAAAGAGUAUUAUUAAAAUACAAUGUUUAUACGUCUAUUUGUGUAUUGUAGAUGUAUCAAGUGAUUUCUAAUUUUUUUCACAUAUGAAUGUGCCAGAUUACUCUAGAACUAGAUGUCUCUUCUUUAAAUAAUUUUAGUUUUCCUGAAUAAAUUUGUAAUGGUUAAAGUACCAAGUAAGUAAGGCGAGAAGGGAUUCUGUUUUUAAAAUCACAUCAGAACUUUUCCUCUACUAAGAUUAUAAAUUAAAUGUAAAAUACUCCUAAUUGCAAUUCUUAAACUUAGGCCUUACAUGUACUUAUUAUGCAACUGCUCCUGGACUCUAUUCACCAUAGAUAUCAGUAAACGUAUGUCCCAGGAUUCACAGGCUUUUGAUUAAUCAAUAUUCUUUUCAAGUUUGCUGUGAAGAGUUUAGUUCUCUUCAAAAUUUCUUAACUAAUCUGAUUUUUAAGAAUUCUCUUUGCAGUGUUUAGCUUCCUAUUCACAUUCUUAAAAUUGCUUUGGUGUUACCAUGAGUCUAAAAUGAAGUUUAGCCUUCCUUUUGUUUCAUUCUGAGAACUUCUAUAUUAUAUUACCUUUAAAAAUUGUUUAUGAUAUUAAAUUUAAAAUACAAACAGCUCUCUUUUUUUUUUUUUUUUUUUUUAAUCAUCCAGCCCAAAGUGGCAAAAACAGCUCUUUUCUCAUUUGGCACCACCAAUAACGCAAGUUAAAAAUAAUGUUGAGUUUAUUAUACUUUUGACCUGUUUAGCUCAACAGGGUGAAGGCAUGUAAAGAAUGUGGACUUCUGAGGAAUUUUCUUUUAAAAAGAACAUAAUGAAGUAACAUUUUAAUUACUCAAGGACUACUUUUGGUUGAAGUUUAUAAUCUAGAUACCUCUACUUUUUGUUUUUGCUGUUCGACAGUUCACAAAGACCUUCAGCAAUUUACAGGGUAAAAUCGUUGAAGUAGUGGAGGUGAAACUGAAAUUUAAAAUUAUUCUGUAAAUACUAUAGGGAAAGAGGCUGAGCUUAGAAUCUUUUGGUUGUUCAUGUGUUCUGUGCUCUUAUCAUCACACAGGUCAUGUGUUGUUACUCAGGAUUCUGGAAGUACUAAGCCGUAGUUAACAGGCUGGAUAGAUCUUCAGCCAAUCUUCUUUCAUUAUACUGCUGCUUUUCUGUUUCUUAAAAAACAAAAAUCAAUGAACAACUUCUUCAGAAGGAAGCACCACUGUUCAAUUGGUUAACUGAAAGUAUGAAUCACUGCCGCUUUGCUUGCCCACCUGUUUGCUUUUUCUCACAGGUUUUAUUUAUCUGAAUGAUUGUUGCAUUUGAAUACUGUAGCCAUGGUGAGUGAGCAGUUGAAGACUUCCUUUCUGCACCUUCAUAGUUAAGGGUUCAUCUUCUCAAGAAAUAAAGUUGUGCUGGGUUGUUUCAAUUCUGUAGAUCACCUAGAAACUAGGUAACAAGGCCCUUGGAUCACAAUGAGCACAUUGCAGGUCUUUGGAAAUGCUGGGAAGGGGUUACAUUCAAGUAACUGCUGACGUCCUUCCUCUCUGUCAGACCCAUGUUGGCCUGUAAUUAUAUUUUUCUGAAUCUAAAAACAAAUAGAAAUUUCUGAUAUCUUUUCAGUCUCCUUCUUUUCUUUCCAUUCAUCACUUAAAUCUCAUUAUUGUAUAACGUUUCAAAUUAUGACCUGGAUUGAAGGAAGUCUGUUUUGUCAGGGACUUUGUUAGGUGAACAUCAGAAUCUCAACUACAACAAAGCUGAAAAAUGAGGCAGCCUUAACAGUAAAUGCUUUUGGGCCGGGCGUGGUGGCUCACGCCUGUAGUCCCAGCACUUUGGGAGGCCGAGGCGGGCGGAUCACGAGGUCAGGAGAUCGAGACCAUCCUGGUUAACACAGUGAAACCCCGUCUCUACUAAAAAUACAAAGAAUUAGCCGGGCGUGGUGGCGGCGCCUGUAGUCCCAGCUGCUCGGGAGGCUGAGGCAGCAGAAUGGCGUGAACCCGGGAGGCGGAGCCUGCAGUGAGCCGAGAUCGUGCCCCUGCACUCCAGCCUGGGCGACAGCGAGACUCCGUCUCAAAAAAAAAAAAAGUGAAUACUUUUGAAAUGAAUGCUUUUUGAAGCUUAGAAGAACCAUUAGGUUUAUGUAAUGCACCCAUACUUAUUCCUUUAAAUAAAUUUUAAUUUAAAAACAUUGAGAUAUUGGCUUCUGUCAACCUGAUUUAAUUAAUUCUUUACAUUAAGCUGAUUUUCCCCCUGGCAGCUGACAAAUAAGUUCAUUGUUCUUGUAGAAGUGAGCUCACAAGGUUAAAUGUGAAUGUUCUCAAAGGUACACAGCCUUGUUUCAGAAGAAUUUUAAUGCCCGCUGUAAAAUCAAUCAUGCAGAGCCAAUUUGAGGUAUGACUCCAGGGUAUGCAAGGUAUGACUUCUCUGGAAGCCAAGUCUUUUCACAGGGCACUGUGGUAAUACCCAUAGCACUAAUCCUCAGUGUGCUGGUUGAAGAAAUAAAAUGUUUUUAAAGAAGGAUAAAGGAGGAAUUAAUUAGAAAAUUUUUUUCCACAUAUUAGCAAAUAAAUGAAAUGUCAUUUUCAUAUUAAGUAAGUAUAGUUAUGAUCUUCGUUUCUACCUACUCUCCUUUUGAAAUAUUCUUUAUUACUAAAUAAUAUUUUAGGAGGAGUUAACAGAAAUAAUUACCUGUAACAUCUGCAGAUAAACUUACAUAGCUAACAUUGUGUGCUGACUUUUUUAAAUGGUGAAGUGGCAUUAAUGAGAUGUUCAGUUUACAGAAUUUGAAGUUUGAGUUCUAUUUUAAUAGUCUGCCGUGUCCCCCAAAUCCCAUUUAGAUAAAUUGAGGUUGAUUUUUCACAUAGACUUGCAAUUUUUAGACACCACAUUUUUUUUAUAGUAACAGCCUCAUUUGCCUGUACAAUAACUAAUAAUACAGUAUUUCAUAGGUACAUUGUAUGUGCACAGGAAAUUUUUCUUUAAAUCUUAAGAGCCUUUAAUAAACGGGAUAUUUUAAUAUUUUAAUGUUACUACAUUUAAAAAAUAGUGUUUUCCUACAAAAUUUUCUGUAUUCAGUAUACGUUAACUAUGAAAAUGUCAAACAAUGAAAUCAUUGAAAUAUAUUUAAGGAAAAAUUACCAACCAAAAGUAAUGAGUACCCUCUAUGUGCAUAUUUACUGGAAUGUUCAUGUGAAAUGGUAACAUUUCCAAUAACAGCAUUUUGAAUCUGGGGUGACACAAACAUGAUUUUUAUUUUUGAGCUAGGGAUUUUGAUGGAGAAGCACCUAGAUGAAGACACCAUUUCAUUCAUGAUAUUUUAAAAUUAGAAAAGUAAAGCUUCUAAAUUGAAACUCUUAACAGGUCACUUCAUGAAAUUUUUAGUUUUAAAUUUAAUUUUACAUGAGAUGUCUUUCUGAAGAGCUACUUUUAUUAACUUUCACUUAGAUCGUUGUAUGCUAGGCAUUCAGUAUUUCUCUACUUGAUUUUCCUAUGCCUAGUUGUGAUUACAGCAAGUAUUUAAUAAUAAAGUCAGUCAUGUGAGAGUAUCCAUUAAUUUCAGUGGGUCCUUGGAAGGCAGGCAGAAGAUUUCUGUCCAAGAGUCUUAUUUUUGACAUGAGAUGAAAUUCUUUUUUUUUUUUUGAGAUGGGGUCUCACUCUGUCACCCAGGCUGGAGUGCAGUGGCAGGAUCUUGGCUCACUGCAACCUCCCAAGCUCAAGCCAUCCUCCCACCUCAGUCUCCUGAGUAGUUGGGACUACUGGCAUGUGCCCCCAUUCCUGAUUAGUUUUUUUGUAUUUUUGGUAGAGAUGGGGUCUUGCUAUAUUGCCUAAUUUUUGUGUUUUUAGUAGAGAUGGGGUUUCACCAUGUUGGCCAGGCUGCUCUUGAACUCCUGAGCUCAAGUAAUCUGCCCGCCCUGGCCUCCCAAAGUGCUGGGAUUACAGGCAUGAGCCACCAUGCCUGGCUAAAACCAAUUCUUUAGAUUGUUUUUGCCACCAUUUGCUUACUUGGAAUAGCUUUCACAUUUAUUUUUCUUAUGAAGAAAUCCAGUGUCAGUCAGACCAUGUAACAUCAAAGCAAAAUUUCAUUGAAGCCUAUCCUUGUCUUAAUUAUUCUAAAAUAAAGUACAAUAAAGUGAAUUAUUUUGCCCUUUGUAGUAGCAUAGUGUUAAGUUAUAUAUAUAUUUUAAUAUGCAUACUCCUAAGUAAAGUUUCAGAGACCACAUGCUGGAGAGCAGUGGCUUUCAGACAGCAUCAGCAUCACCUGAAGGCCUUGUUGAAUACACAUUAUUGGAAGAGAGGGGAGAACACAGGCUCAUGCCUGUAAUUCCAGUGCUUUGGGAGACUGAGGCAGGAGGAUCACGUGAGCCCAGGAGUUCAAGAUCAGGCUGGGCAAUACAGCAAGACCCCUGUCUCUACAAAAACAAAAACAAAAAACAAACAGGCAUGGUAGUGCAUACCUGUAGUCUGAGCUGCUUGGGAGUCUGAGGCAGGAGGAUCACUUGAACCCAGGAGUUCGAGGCUGCAGUGAGUUAUUAUUGGGCCACUGCAGUCCAGCCUGGGCAGCAAAGUGAGACCCUGUCUGUUAAAAAAACAAAACCAAAAACUUGAUUGCUGGGGGCCACCCUAGAGUUUCUGAUUCAGUAGGUCUGGCGGUGGGGAUGGUGGGCCUGGUAAUUUGCCUUUCUAACAAGCGUCCAGGUAAUGCCCCAGCUGCUGGUCCCAGGACCACACUUUGCAGAUUAUUACUCUGAGAAGAGCACUAACUCUGACGUUGGAUUCCUUCUGUUCCUCAUUAGUGAAUUUAUUUGGGGGAGAUUAUUCAAUCUGGUAGAUCCGCAUUUACUUAGCUGUGAAGUGGAGGUUAAUGCAACCUGCCUGAGACUGUGAGAAUGAGAAACUCUAAUUGAAAUACCAGGCCCAGCGUGCCUGGAUGCUUGAAAAAUGCUGACUCCCAUGGUCCGUCCUUCCCUCACUCUUCUCAGCUAUAAAGUGAGAAGCGAAAUUCAGUAUCUUUUAAGAUUCCUCUCAGGUGUAAAAUGCUGUGAUUCUAAAAGUUUAAUUUUGUAGUUCCAGAGACAAUGCCAAACACCUGUGUGUGCUUAGUGCUUUGUAAAGAGUGGUAAUAACAGUGACACCACAUAGGCCGUAGUUUUGUAGUUCCAGAGACAAUGCCAAACACCUGUGUGUACUUAGUGCUUUGUAAAGAGUGAAUAACAGUGACACCACAUAGGCCAUAGUUUUGUAGUUCCAGAGACAAUGCCAAACACCUAUGUGUACUUAGUGCUUUGUAAAGAGUGGUAAUAACAGUGACACCACAUAGGCCGUAAUUUUGUUUUUGCUUUUGUUAGGGUGUUCAGCAUCUUGACUCCUUAAAUAAGGUUUUCAGUCAGAUUUAUAAAGCAGCAUUGAAGAAGUUGUAUUAUAUUUGAGUACAGUUGGAAUCCAUGGCAGUUUUAUGGAGGCCAAAUAUAUCAGAUGAAUAGGCUAAUUUCCCUGAGUUGCUGGCCUUAUUAGUCCCUACUCUGUUGCCCCCUGGUUACCUAAUGCAUGUUCAAAAGGUAUAGUUUUCAUCACCUGCUUGAUCUUGAUUUUCAGACAGCAUCAAAUCAGUUGCAAAACAAAUCCAAGCUAAAAUUUUGAGUGUAUGAUUAAUUUACUAUAGCAUGUAAUUAUGCAGUAUUUUAUUUUUUAUUUUUUAUUUUUUUUGAGACAGAGUCUCACUCCAUUGCCCAGGCUGAAGUGCAGUGGCACGAUCUCGGCUCACUCUAACCUCUGCCUCCUGGGUUCAAGUGAUUCUCCUGCCUCAGCCUCCCGAAUAGCUGGGAUUACAGACAUGCACCACCACGCCCAGCUAAUUUUUUGUAUUUAUAGUAGAGAGGAGGUUUUACCAUGUUGGCCAGGUUGGUCUUGAACUCUUGACCUCAAGUGAUCUACACGCCUCGGCCUCCCAAAGUGCUGGGAUUACGGGUGUGAGCCACUGCGCCCAGCUAUCCAGUAUUUUAUUUAAAAGUUGUCACUAGGGUGUUCACUAUUGUGAAUUUAUAAUCUUAAAAGUUGGGGAUGCUAAAAGUACCAGACUAAAAUACUACGAGGUUUUCUCAUCUUUUAAUUCCAUUUUGUUAGAAAAAAAUAAUCACAACCGGGGUUCUUUUACCUUUCCCCAGCCAUCUAGACUGCUUUACUGCAAUGUUGGGAAGAUUGCAUACAAUAAAAACUGUAGCUAGUUGAUUGGGAUUUGGGAAAAUUGAAUCAAGCAUUUGCAUUCAUCCAGAAUGGUCUUAAACUGCUGACUGUGGGGUGCCCACAGGAUGAGCACUGGUGGCAUGGGUGGGAGGAAUUUCCUUGGAUACUGCAAUUGCAUUUGAAAGAUCUAUUUUCCAAAACCUGAGCAGAGAGAGGCUAGGAGGAAUGCAGACAGGACAUUGAAAAUGCGAAUUCCCUUUACUAGUAGAACAUGAAAUAUCUGAUAAUGGUUUAAAAAAAAUAAGUGCCAGGAUACAUUGUAGUAUAAAGGUUCAACUAGUAUAAUUUAAAAUGAGUCUUUAUAUUCAGGCCAGGUGCGGUGGCUCACACCUGUAAUCCCAGCACUUUGGGAGUCCGAGGCGGGUGGAUCACCUGAGAUUAGGAGUUCAAAACCAGUGUGACCAACAUGGAGAAACCCCUUCUCUACUAAAAAUACAAAAAAUUAGCCAGGCAUGGUGGUGCACGCCUGUAGUCCCAGCUACUUGUGAGGCUGAGGUAGGAGAAUCGCUUGAACCCAAGAGGCAGAGGUUGCAGUGAGCUGAGAUCACACCACUGCACUCCAGCCUGGGUGACAGAGCGAGACCCUGUUUCAAAAAAAUAAGAAAUAAAAAGUGAGUCUUCAUAUUCAAAUUAGUAUAUGAGGUUAGGCAACAAUUCUUAUAUGGGACCAGGUAUAUUUAAUUUGCCUUUCUUUGCAGUCAUCCUAGUAAAUCCUUGUAAAGGGUUAUUUUAUAUACAAUUUUGUAGUAUAUUCUAAAUCCCCUUUGGCAAAUAAAGCUGAAGUUAUCUAGUGUCAGCAUACUGUGAUUUGUAUAUUUAUAUAAGACAAGAUUGCAUCAUUCUGAUUAAGUUGCAGCAUUUUAGUUUUAUCUGAUAGGCCUGUAUUGAGUAAUCAGUAGCUAUGUGCAAAUAUUAAGUCAACUUAAUUACCAGACCCAGAAGGCCAGAGGUAAUCAAAGAGUACUUUCGGAAGAUGAAAUAUUUAUAAUGAGUUAUGGAAACAAUGUUUUAGAAAUGUUUUUCUUGGUGUAAUUUAAUGCAGAUUUUUACCUCAAUUUUGUUAAAAAACUUGAUAAUUUGAUCCCUCCAUCUAUUUAAUAUUUAAUAUUUUCAGAUUCUAGAGUAUUUAAAAUUUAAACACAAUUAUAAAAUUAAUUAUAAUUCCUACUUAUGUUAGCUAUGAUUUAGGGCCAAAACUACCCUGGUUUUGUCUUGCAACUUGAAACAUUGUGUAUUUUAAACUAUAUAAUUUGGGAACAUUAUUUUAUAGACUGUGGAUAACCAAAUAUAAGAUUUGUGAUUUUUAAUGCUUCAUUUGUGUAAAAUCAUUUGUAUAUUCUAUUUAUAGUAUGCAUUUUCUAGCUCAUUAAAAGUACAGAAAAACCUCAAAUCUGUCCUUAUACAAAUAUUUGAUUUCUAGUUUCCUUUUAUUAAAACAUUUUCACUCAUUCAUUCUUUCA